GUUUGUGUUGGAAAAUCCAACUGCGCCACUGGGCGGAGCGGCCCCCCCAGCCCCGGCCUGGGAGAAGGGGGGGCCGCUCGACCCCCUGGGAUACCUUGGGGAGCCUGAACACCUGGGACCCCCCCCAGAACCAGGUUCCCCCCAGGGCAACAUGCCAGCCCCGUAGCACUGCCCACCCCACCCACUGUGGUCUGUUGUACCCCACUGCUGGGGUGGUGGUUCCAAUGAGACAGGGCACACCAAACUCCAUCUGGCUGUUACUGAGGCGGAGACACGGGUGAUGAUUGGCUUUCUGGGGAGAGAGGAAGUCCUGUGAUUGGCCAGAUCUCUGGAGCUUGCCGACGCGGUGUGAGGACGCUCCCACGGAGGCCGGAAUUGGCUGUGAAAGGACUGAGGCAGCCAUCUGGGGGUAGCGGGCACUCUUAUCAGAGCGGCUGGAGCCGGACCAUCGUCCCAGAGAGCUGGGGCAGGGGGCCGUGCCCAAUCUCCAGGGCUCCUGGGGCCACUGCUGACCUGGCUGGAUGCAUCGGGCAGUGGACCCUCCAGGGGCCCGCGCUGCACGGGAAGCCUUUGCCCUUGGGGGCCUGAGCUGUGCUGGGGCCUGGAGCUCCUGCCCGCCUCAUCCCCCUCCUCGUAGCGCAUGGCUGCCUGGAGGCAGAUGCUCAGCCAGCAUUGGGCAGCCCCCGCUUCCUGCUCCCCUACCCCCUUCACAUGGCAGUAGUUCUGGGCACCCCAGCAAACCAUAUUAUGCUCCAGGGGCGCCCACUCCAAGACCCCUCCAUGGGAAGCUGGAAUCCCUGCAUGGCUGUGUGCAGGCAUUGCUCCGGGAGCCAGCCCAGCCAGGGCUUUGGGAACAGCUUGGGCAACUGUACGAGUCAGAGCACGAUAGUGAGGAGGCCACACGCUGCUACCACAGCGCCCUUCGAUACGGAGGAAGCUUCGCUGAGCUGGGGCCCCGCAUUGGCCGACUGCAGCAGGCCCAGCUCUGGAACUUUCAUACUGGCUCCUGCCAGCACCGAGCCAAGGUCCUGCCCCCACUGGAGCAAGUGUGGAACUUGCUACACCUUGAGCACAAACGGAACUAUGGAGCCAAGCGGGGAGGUCCCCCGGUGAAGCGAGCUGCUGAACCCCCAGUGGUGCAGCCUGUGCCUCCUGCAGCACUCUCAGGCCCCUCAGGGGAGGAGGGCCUCAGCCCUGGAGGCAAGCGAAGGAGAGGCUGCAACUCUGAACAGACUGGCCUUCCCCCAGGGCUGCCACUGCCUCCACCACCAUUACCACCACCACCACCACCACCACCACCACCACCACCACCCCUGCCUGGCCUGGCUACCAGCCCCCCAUUUCAGCUAACCAAGCCAGGGCUGUGGAGUACCCUGCAUGGAGAUGCCUGGGGCCCAGAGCGCAAGGGUUCAGCACCCCCAGAGCGCCAGGAGCAGCGGCACUCGCUGCCUCACCCAUAUCCAUACCCAGCUCCAGCGUACACCGCGCACCCCCCUGGCCACCGGCUGGUCCCGGCUGCUCCCCCAGGCCCAGGCCCCCGCCCCCCAGGAGCAGAGAGCCAUGGCUGCCUGCCUGCCACCCGUCCCCCCGGAAGUGACCUUAGAGAGAGCAGAGUUCAGAGGUCGCGGAUGGACUCCAGCGUUUCACCAGCAGCAACCACCGCCUGCGUGCCUUACGCCCCUUCCCGGCCCCCUGGCCUCCCCGGCACCACCACCAGCAGCAGCAGUAGCAGCAGCAGCAACACUGGUCUCCGGGGCGUGGAGCCGAACCCAGGCAUUCCCGGCGCUGACCAUUACCAAACUCCCGCGCUGGAGGUCUCUCACCAUGGCCGCCUGGGGCCCUCGGCACACAGCAGUCGGAAACCGUUCUUGGGGGCUCCCGCUGCCACUCCCCACCUAUCCCUGCCACCUGGACCUUCCUCACCCCCUCCACCCCCCUGUCCCCGCCUCUUACGCCCCCCACCACCCCCUGCCUGGUUGAAGGGUCCGGCCUGCCGGGCAGCCCGAGAGGAUGGAGAGAUCUUAGAAGAGCUCUUCUUUGGGACUGAGGGACCCCCCCGCCCUGCCCCACCACCCCUCCCCCAUCGCGAGGGCUUCUUGGGGCCUCCGGCCUCCCGCUUUUCUGUGGGCACUCAGGAUUCUCACACCCCUCCCACUCCCCCAACCCCAACCACCAGCAGUAGCAACAGCAACAGUGGCAGCCACAGCAGCAGCCCUGCUGGGCCUGUGUCCUUUCCCCCACCACCCUAUCUGGCCAGAAGUAUAGACCCCCUUCCCCGGCCUCCCAGCCCAGCACAGAACCCCCAGGACCCACCUCUUGUACCCCUGACUCUUGCCCUGCCUCCAGCCCCUCCUUCCUCCUGCCACCAAAAUACCUCAGGAAGCUUCAGGCGCCCGGAGAGCCCCCGGCCCAGGGUCUCCUUCCCAAAGACCCCCGAGGUGGGGCCGGGGCCACCCCCAGGCCCCCUGAGUAAAGCCCCCCAGCCUGUGCCGCCCGGGGUUGGGGAGCUGCCUGCCCGAGGCCCUCGACUCUUUGAUUUUCCCCCCACUCCGCUGGAGGACCAGUUUGAGGAGCCAGCCGAAUUCAAGAUCCUACCUGAUGGGCUGGCCAACAUCAUGAAGAUGCUGGACGAAUCCAUUCGCAAGGAAGAGGAACAGCAACAACACGAAGCAGGCGUGGCCCCCCAACCCCCGCUGAAGGAGCCCUUUGCAUCUCUGCAGUCUCCUUUCCCCACCGACACAGCCCCCACCACUACUGCUCCUGCUGUCGCCGUCACCACCACCACCACCACCACCACCACCACCACGGCCACCCAGGAAGAGGAGAAGAAGCCACCACCAGCCCUACCACCACCACCGCCUCUAGCCAAGUUCCCUCCACCCUCUCAGCCACAGCCACCACCACCCCCACCCCCCAGCCCGGCCAGCCUGCUCAAAUCCUUGGCCUCCGUGCUGGAGGGACAAAAGUACUGUUAUCGGGGGACUGGAGCAGCUGUUUCCACCCGGCCUGGGCCCUUGCCCACCACUCAGUAUUCCCCUGGCCCCCCAUCAGGUGCUACCGCCCUGCCGCCCACCUCAGCGGCCCCUAGCGCCCAGGGCUCCCCACAGCCCUCUGCUUCCUCGUCAUCUCAGUUCUCUACCUCAGGCGGGCCCUGGGCCCGGGAGCGCAGGGCGGGCGAAGAGCCAGUCCCGGGCCCCAUGACCCCCACCCAACCGCCCCCACCCCUAUCUCUGCCCCCUGCUCGCUCUGAGUCUGAGGUGCUAGAAGAGAUCAGCCGGGCUUGCGAGACCCUUGUGGAGCGGGUGGGCCGGAGUGCCACUGACCCAGCCGACCCAGUGGACACAGCAGAGCCAGCGGACAGUGGGACUGAGCGACUGCUGCCCCCCGCACAGGCCAAGGAGGAGGCUGGCGGGGUGGCGGCAGUGUCAGGCAGCUGUAAGCGGCGACAGAAGGAGCAUCAGAAGGAGCAUCGGCGGCACAGGCGGGCCUGUAAGGACAGUGUGGGUCGUCGGCCCCGUGAGGGCAGGGCAAAGGCCAAGGCCAAGGUCCCCAAAGAAAAGAGCCGCCGGGUGCUGGGGAACCUGGACCUGCAGAGCGAGGAGAUCCAGGGUCGUGAGAAGUCCCGGCCCGAUCUUGGCGGGGCCUCCAAGGCCAAGCCACCCACAGCUCCAGCCCCUCCAUCAGCUCCUGCACCUUCUGCCCAGCCCACACCCCCGUCAGCCUCUGUCCCUGGAAAGAAGGCUCGGGAGGAAGCCCCAGGGCCACCGGGUGUCAGCCGGGCCGACAUGCUGAAGCUGCGCUCACUUAGUGAGGGGCCCCCCAAGGAGCUGAAGAUCCGGCUCAUCAAGGUAGAGAGUGGUGACAAGGAGACCUUUAUCGCCUCUGAGGUGGAAGAGCGGCGGCUGCGCAUGGCAGACCUCACCAUCAGCCACUGUGCUGCUGACGUCGUGCGCGCCAGCAGGAAUGCCAAGGUGAAAGGGAAGUUUCGAGAGUCCUACCUUUCCCCUGCCCAGUCUGUGAAACCGAAGAUCAACACUGAGGAGAAGCUGCCCCGGGAAAAACUCAACCCCCCUACACCCAGCAUCUAUCUGGAGAGCAAACGGGAUGCCUUCUCACCUGUCCUGCUGCAGUUCUGUACAGACCCUCGAAAUCCCAUCACAGUGAUCCGGGGCCUGGCGGGCUCCCUGCGGCUCAACUUGGGCCUCUUCUCCACCAAGACCCUGGUGGAAGCGAGUGGCGAACACACCGUGGAAGUUCGCACCCAGGUGCAGCAGCCCUCAGAUGAGAACUGGGAUCUGACAGGCACUCGGCAGAUCUGGCCUUGUGAGAGCUCCCGUUCCCACACCACCAUUGCCAAGUACGCACAGUACCAGGCCUCAUCCUUCCAGGAGUCUCUGCAGGAGGAGAAGGAGAGUGAGGAUGAGGAGUCAGAGGAGCCAGACAGCACCACUGGAACCCCUCCUAGCAGCGCACCAGACCCGAAGAACCAUCACAUCAUCAAGUUUGGCACCAACAUCGACUUGUCUGAUGCUAAGCGGUGGAAGCCCCAGCUGCAGGAGCUGCUGAAGCUGCCCGCCUUCAUGCGGGUAACAUCCACGGGCAACAUGCUGAGCCACGUGGGCCACACCAUCCUGGGCAUGAACACGGUGCAGCUGUACAUGAAGGUGCCCGGCAGCCGAACGCCAGGCCACCAGGAGAAUAACAACUUCUGCUCCGUCAACAUCAACAUUGGCCCAGGCGACUGCGAGUGGUUCGCGGUGCACGAGCACUACUGGGAGACCAUCAGCGCUUUCUGUGAUCGGCACGGCGUGGACUACUUGACGGGUUCCUGGUGGCCAAUCCUGGAUGAUCUCUAUGCAUCCAAUAUUCCUGUGUACCGCUUCGUGCAGCGACCCGGAGACCUCGUGUGGAUUAAUGCGGGGACUGUGCACUGGGUGCAGGCCACCGGCUGGUGCAACAACAUUGCCUGGAACGUGGGGCCCCUCACCGCCUAUCAGUACCAGCUGGCCCUGGAACGAUACGAGUGGAAUGAGGUGAAGAACGUCAAAUCCAUCGUGCCCAUGAUUCACGUGUCAUGGAACGUGGCUCGCACGGUCAAAAUCAGCGACCCCGACUUGUUCAAGAUGAUCAAGUUCUGCCUGCUGCAGUCCAUGAAGCACUGCCAGGUGCAACGCGAGAGCCUGGUGCGGGCAGGGAAGAAAAUCGCUUACCAGGGCCGUGUCAAGGACGAGCCAGCCUACUACUGCAACGAGUGCGAUGUGGAGGUGUUUAACAUCCUGUUCGUGACAAGUGAGAAUGGCAGCCGCAACACGUACCUGGUACACUGCGAGGGCUGUGCCCGGCGCCGCAGCGCAGGCCUGCAGGGCGUGGUGGUGCUGGAGCAGUACCGCACUGAGGAGCUGGCUCAGGCCUACGACGCCUUCACGCUGGCCCCAGCCAGCACGUCGCGAUGAGGCCGGACGCCCCGCCCGCCUGCCUGCCCGCGCAAGGCGCCGCGGGGCCACCAGCACAUGCCUGGGCUGGACCUAGGUCCCGCCUGUGGCCGAGAAGGGGGUCGGGCCCAGCCCUUCCACCCCAUUGGCAGCUCCCCUCACUUAAUUUAUUAAGAAAAACUUUUUUUUUUUUUUUAGCAAAUAUGAGGAAAAAAGGAAAAAAAAUGGGAGACGGGGGAGGGGGCUGGCAGCCCCUCGCCCACCAGCGCCUCCCCUCACCGACUUUGGCCUUUUUAGCAACAGACACAAGGACCAGGCUCCGGCGGCGGCGGGGGUCACAUACGGGUUCCCUCACCCUGCCAGCCGCCCGCCCGCCCGGCGCAGAUGCACGCGGCUCGUGUAUGUACAUAGACGUUACGGCAGCCGAGGUUUUUAAUGAGAUUCUUUCUAUGGGCUUUACCCCUCCCCCGGAACCUCCUUUUUUACUUCCAAUGCUAGCUGUGACCCCUGUACAUGUCUCUUUAUUCACUUGGUUAUGAUUUGUAUUUUUUGUUCUUUUCUUGUUUUUUUGUUUUUAAUUUAUAACAGUCCCACUCACCUCUAUUUAUUCAUUUUUGGGAAAACCCGACCUCCCACACCCCCAAGCCAUCCUGCCCGCCCCUCCAGGGACCGCCCGUCGCCGGGCUCUCCCCGCGCCCCAGUGUGUGUCCGGGCCCGGCCCGACCGUCUCCACCCGUCCGCCCGCGGCUCCAGCCGGGUUCUCAUGGUGCUCAAACCCGCUCCCCUCCCCUACGUCCUGCACUUUCUCGGACCAGUCCCCCCACUCCCGACCCGACCCCAGCCCCACCUGAGGGUGAGCAACUCCUGUACUGUAGGGGAAGAAGUGGGAACUGAAAUGGUAUUUUGUAAAAAAAAUAAAUAAAAUAAAAAAAUUAAAGGUUUUAAAGAAAGAACUAUGAGGAAAAGGAACCCCGUCCUUCCCAGCCCCGGCCAACUUUAAAAAACACAGACCUUCACCCCCACCCCCUUUUCUUUUUAAGUGUGAAACAACCCAGGGCCAGGGCCUCACUGGGGCAGGGACACCCCGGGGUGAGUUUCUCUGGGGCUUUAUUUUCGUUUUGUUGGUUGUUUUUUCUCCACGCUGGGGCUGCGGAGGGGUGGGGGGUUUACAGUCCCGCACCCUCGCACUGCACUGUCUCUCUGCCCCAGGGGCAGAGGGGUCUUCCCAACCCUACCCCUAUUUUCGGUGAUUUUUGUGUGAGAAUAUUAAUAUUAAAAAUAAACGGAGAAAAAAAA